AGUCCUCGGCGUGUGCUGGCAGCUUCGGAGCCCACCGAGCCGGGCGGCUAGGAUGAUGAACCGGACGACCCCCGACCAGGAGCUGGCGCCAGCGUCGGAGCCCGUGUGGGAGCGGCCGUGGUCGGUGGAGGAGAUCCGCAGGAGCAGCCAGAGCUGGUCGCUGGCGGCCGACGCGGGCCUACUACAGUUUCUACAGGAAUUCUCACAGCAAACUAUCUCUAGGACCCAUGAAAUCAAGAAACAAGUGGACGGACUAAUUCGGGAAACCAAAGCCACAGAUUGUCGCCUGCAUAAUGUCUUCAAUGACUUCCUUAUGCUCUCUAAUACCCAGUUCAUUGAGAAUCGUGUAUAUGAUGAAGAAGUGGAGGAGCCAGUACUCAAGGCUGAGGCAGAAAAAACAGAGCAGGAGAAGACACGAGAGCAGAAAGAAGUAGAUCUCAUUCCUAAAGUCCAGGAGGCUGUGAACUAUGGCUUACAAGUAUUGGACAGUGCCUUUGAGCAACUUGAUAUCAAAGCAGGAAACUCAGACUCCGAGGAAGAUGAUGCUAAUGGGCGGGUGGAACUGAUCCUUGAACCAAAGGAUCUAUACAUUGAUCGUCCUUUACCAUAUCUCAUUGGGUCAAAGCUGUUCAUGGAACAAGAAGAUGUAGGUCUUGGAGAGCUGUCCAGUGAAGAAGGCUCUGUAGGCAGUGAUCGUGGCAGUAUUGUGGACACUGAGGAAGAGAAAGAAGAGGAGGAGUCAGAUGAAGAUUUUGCCCAUCAUAGUGACAAUGAACAAAACCGGCACACCACACAAAUGAGUGAUGAGGAAGAGGAUGAUGAUGGCUGUGACCUUUUCGCUGACUCUGAGAAGGAGGAGGAAGAUAUUGAGGACAUUGAAGAAAAUACUAGACCUAAAAGAAGCAGACCUACAUCGUUUGCAGAUGAGCUGGCUGCCCGCAUCAAGGGGGAUGCCGUGGGUCGAGUGGACGAGGAGCCGACAACCUUACCCUCAGGAGAAGCAAAACCUCGGAAGACACUCAAAGAGAAGAAGGAAAGGAGAACUCCUUCAGACGAUGAAGAGGAUAACUUAUUCGCACCCCCCAAGCUGACCGACGAGGACUUCUCGCCAUUUGGCUCUGGAGGUGGCCUGUUCAGUGGGGGCAAGGGGCUCUUUGAUGAUGAGGACGAGGAGAGUGACCUCUUCACGGAAGCCCCCCAGGAUCGGCAAGCUGGAGCCUCUGUUAAGGAGGAGUCUUCAUCAUCCAAACCUGGAAAGAAAAUCCCAGCAGGAGCUGUUUCUGUAUUUUUAGGAGACACGGAUGUGUUUGGUGCUGCCUCCGUUCCAUCAAUGAAGGAGCCACAGAAGCCUGAGCAGCCCACUCCAAGGAAAAGCCCCUAUGGUCCCCCUCCCACUGGCCUCUUUGAUGAUGAUGAUGGUGAUGAUGAUGACGACUUUUUCUCGGCACCCCACAGCAAACCUUCUAAAACAGGCAAAGUCCAAUCCACUGCCGAUAUCUUUGGUGACGAAGAAGGAGAUCUGUUCAAAGAAAAAGCCGUAGCAUCGCCAGAAGCCACUGUGAGUCAGACAGAUGAAAAUAAAGCAAGAGCAGAAAAAAAGGUUACCUUAUCUUCCAGCAAAAAUCUCAAGCCCUCAUCAGAAACAAAGACUCAAAAAGGCUUAUUUUCAGAUGAGGAGGACUCUGAGGAUUUGUUUUCUUCUCAAAGUGCGAGUAAGUUAAAAGGUGCGUCUCUGCUGCCUGGCAAGCUCCCCACGUUGGUUUCCCUGUUUGAUGAUGAAGAUGAAGAGGAUAAUCUUUUUGGGGGUACAGCUGCUAAGAAGCAGACAUUGUGUCUACAAGCUCAGAGAGAAGAGAAAGCAAAAGCCUCCGAGCUCUCCAAAAAGAAAGCAUCUGCCCUGUUGUUCAGCAGUGAUGAGGAGGACCAGUGGAAUAUUCCUGCUUCACAGACCCACUUAGCAUCUGACAGCAGGUCUAAAGGAGAACCCAGGGAUUCUGGGACCCUCCAGAGCCAGGAGGCCAAGGCUGUGAAAAAGACCAGUCUCUUUGAGGAAGACGAAGAAGAUGAUCUUUUUGCCAUUGCCAAGGACAGCCAAAAGAAGACCCAGAGAGUGUCACUCCUCUUUGAAGACGAUGUUGAUAGCGGAGGCUCUCUGUUUGGCUCUCCUCCCACAUCUGUUCCUCCUGCAACAAAGAAAAAAGAGACUGUCUCUGAGGCACCACCUUUGCUGUUCAGCGAUGAAGAAGAGAAGGAGGCACAACUUGGAGUGAAGUCUGUGGAUAAGAAGGUUGAGAGUGCCAAGGAGUCAUUAAAAUUUGGGAGAACUGAUGUGGCUGAGUCAGAAAAGGAAGGACUUUUGACUAGAUCUGCUCAGGAAACAGUCAAGCAUUCUGAUUUAUUUUCUUCAUCAUCCCCAUGGGACAAAGGAACCAAGCCUAGAACCAAAACUGUUCUUAGCUUGUUUGAUGAGGAAGAGGAUAAAAUGGAAGAUCAAAACAUUAUCCAGGCUCCACAGAAAGAAGUAGGAAAGGGCCGCGAUCCUGAUGCCCACCCCAAGAGCACAGGUGUCUUCCAGGAUGAAGAGCUGCUUUUCAGCCACAAGCUCCAAAAGGACAAUGACCCAGAUGUUGACCUUUUUGCUGGCACCAAAAAAACCAAGCUGUUAGAGCCAAGUGUUGGGAGCCUGUUUGGGGAUGAUGAAGAUGAUGAUCUUUUCAGCUCUGCCAAGUCCCAGCCUUUGGUACAAGAGAAAAAGAGAGUAGUGAAAAAAGACCACUCUGUUGACUCUUUCAAAAACCAGAAACAUCCUGAAUCCAUUCAAGGUAGUAAAGAAAAAGGCAUAUGGAAGCCGGAAACACCUCAGGACUCAUCAGGUCUCGCUCCAUUUAAAACCAAAGAACCAUCCACUCGGAUCGGGAAGAUACAAGCAAAUUUAGCGAUCAACCCAGCGGCCUUGCUGCCCACAGCGGCUUCCCAGAUCUCUGAAGUAAAGCCUGUUUUGCCAGAAUUGGCUUUUCCUUCAUCUGAACACAGAAGGAGCCACGGUCUGGAAAGUGUGCCUGUCCUUCCCGGGAGUGGGGAGGCCGGUGUGAGUUUUGAUCUUCCAGCUCAGGCAGACACCUUACACAGUGCAAACAAGAGCCGUGUCAAGAUGAGAGGGAAGCGUAGACCGCAGACCCGUGCAGCUAGGCGGCUGGCUGCUCAGGAGUCCAGCGAGACUGAGGACAUGAGCGUCCCCAGAGGACCCAUUGCACAGUGGGCUGAUGGCGCCAUUUCCCCAAAUGGCCAUCGGCCACAGCUCAGAGCAGCCAGUGGAGAAGACAGCACUGAGGAGGCCCUGGCAGCUGCCGCUGCACCUUGGGAAGGUGGUCCUGUGCCUGGAGUGGACAGAAGCCCCUUUGCAAAGUCUCUGGGUCAUUCCAGAGGGGAGGCUGACCUUUUUGAUUCUGGGGACAUCUUUUCCACGGGCACUGGAUCUCAGUCUGUGGAGAGAACAAAACCCAAGGCAAAGAUAGCAGAGAAUCCUGCCAACCCACCAGUGGGUGGUAAAGCAAAGAGCCCCAUGUUUCCUGCUCUAGGUGAGGCCAGCAGUGAUGAUGAUCUCUUUCAGUCUGCUAAACCAAAACCAGCAAAGAAAACAAAUCCCUUUCCUCUCCUGGAAGAUGAGGAUGACCUCUUUACAGAUCAGAAAGUCAAGAAGAAUGAGACAAAAUCCAAUAGUCAGCAGGAUGUCAUAUUAACAACACAAGAUAUUUUUGAGGAUGAUAUAUUUGCUACGGAAGCAAUUAAACCCUCUCAGAAAACCAGAGAGAAGGAGAAAACAUUGGAAUCUAAUUUAUUUGAUGAUAACAUUGAUAUCUUUGCUGACUUAACUGUAAAACCAAAAGAAAAGUCCAAAAAGAAAGUGGAAGCCAAGUCUAUAUUUGAUGAUGAUAUGGAUGACAUCUUCUCCUCUGGUAUCCAGGCUAAGACAACCAAACCAAAAAGCCGAUCUGCACAGGCCGCACCUGAACCAAGAUUUGAACACAAGGUGUCCAACAUCUUUGAUGAUCCCCUGAAUGCCUUUGGAGGCCAGUAGAGCACACAGGGUAUCCACAUGUUACCCUGCAGCUACAUUGUUGAGUUAGUGAUGAUGUUGUAUAUGCUGAUGGUCUUAACUGGAUUACAAAAAGCAAAUACUAGAACAGCUAGCUCAUCGUUCACCCAAUGUACUUGGUAUUUUUCUGCACUGGUUUAAUCAUGCUUAAUACUACAAAACAAAAAUAAAUAUUUCACAGUGGUUGGUUUGUUUUGUUUUUAAACCACAGUUUGAUUUAGUUAGCCUUGCUGGGGCCAUAAUAUGCUUCAGGGUGUGUAAAAGAAGAAAUCUCUUUGUGGCUUUCAUGGGCAGGGAAUCCCAGAGAUAGCAAAUGCCACCUGACCAGAAGUCUUUGUUAUAUGGAUGGGAACCCUAACUUAGGGCCUGGGCAGGGGAAAGAGAAAGAAGGUGAGAGAUUAUACUUCAUGAGUCUUAGCAAUAUGGGAGCAGGUUUUCACUGAAUUCUGAGGGUGCCUCUGCAUGUCCUCCAAGGCAAAGUUUGGCAAACUGUGGCCCCCCCACUGUCAUAUUUUGUUAAUAAAAUUUUAUUGGAACACAACCACA